UCUAUACCUGCCCCUCCCCACUCCCAUCCUGACCACACCUGACCCUCCCCACUCCCAUUGCCGACCACAUCUGACCUUCUCACCCUCCCUCCAUAAACCUGCCCCUCCCCACUCCCAUCCUGACCACACCUGGCCCUCCCCACUCCCAUCCUGACCACACCUGGCCCUCCCCACUCCCAUUGCUGACCCUCCCGCCACUCCAAGGUGCUGCGCUUCCCGGCUGUCCCAACGCCAUAUGGGGUUGGCCGUAUGCACCAGUUUGCUAGGGGCACUGGGUCCCACUCCUGACUUUGCUUUGCUCAGGCUGUUUUUCUGGUCUUGGUUUCCUCCACUUAAUCUGUCCAAAUGAGCUUUCCCUGGAGGGCCUGGCUUGAGCCUCACAGUGUUUGCAUCCUGCAGUUUAGCACCUGACUUGAGAAGGUCUUUAGAAAGCACUUGGCCGGUUCUACAGUGUGAAACAAGAAAUUCGGAUCUUUUGAUAGUCAUUGAAACUUUUUCUUUUCAAAGUGUUUAGACAUGAUUGUGCUGGCUCUAGUACUUUCUGCACUUUUUUGACUGGUGGCCACUUGUCACUUGUCAAAGGACUGGAAAUUGGGCCUGUCGGAUACGUCAGUGUGGCGCGGGACAGGCCAAGUGGCCCUCAUUCAAAAUGUGUGGGACCAGAAGAAGUGUUUCCGAUGUUGAAUUGUUUCAUAUUUUCGAAUGUUCGUGUUUUGUAUGGACCGGUUCAGCAAGAUAAUCCAGUGGGCAUUUUCUUUCAGCGUCAUCUCAGUGCUCAAAACGUUUUGGAUUUUGGAGCAUUUUGGAUUUCAGGUUUUUGGAUGAGGGAUGCUCAGCCUGUAGUUAAUGGCCCCCAGCGGUGAUCAGCUUUCCUGAACUUGCCUUUUACAUGGCACUUCCAGACGGCUUUUGUUACACACCAGCCUCCCUGCGAGCCUCCCACCAUAAGAGGCACAUACAUGCAAAUGAAUGCAAAUGAAAUCCCAUCAGAAAUGGGGCUCCUCAGCUGCAGUAGCCUCAUCUGAGGCGUGGCCUCGGGCAGGUGAGAAGACACCUGAGGCGUGGCCUCGGGCAGGUGAGAAGACACCUGAGGCCGUGGCCUCGGGCAGGUGAGAAGACACCUUCAGGCGUGGCCUCGGGCAGGUGAGAAGACACCUGAGGCGUGGCCUCGGGCAGGUGAGAAGACACCUGAGGCGUGGCCGCGGGCAGGUGAGAAGACACCUUCAGGCGUAGCCUCGGGCAGGUGAGAAAGACACCUGAGGCGUGGCCUUGGGCAGGUGAGAAGACACCUGAGGCAUGGCCUCGGGCAGGUGAGAAGACACCUUCAGGCGUAGCCUCGGGCAGGUGAGAAAGACACCUGAGGCGUGGCCUCGGGCAGGUGAGAAGACACCUGAGGCGUGGCCUCGGGCAGGUGAGAAGACACCUGAGGCGUGGCCGCGGGCAGGUGAGAAGACACCUUCAGGCGUAGCCUCAGGCAGGUGAGAAAGACACCUGAGGCGUGGCCUCGGGCAGGUGAGAAGACACCUGAGGCAUGGCCUCGGGCAGGUGAGAAGACACCUUCAGGCGUAGCCUCGGGCAGGUGAGAAAGACACCUGAGGCGUGGCCUCGGGCAGGUGAGAAGACACCUGAGGCGUGGCCUCGGGCAGGUGAGAAGACACCUGAGGCGUGGCCUCGGGCAGGGGAGAAGACACCUUCAGGCAUAGCCUCGGGCAGGUGAGAAAGACACCUGAGGCAUGGCCUCGGGCAGGUGAGAAGACACCUUCAGGCGUAGCCUCGGGCAGGUGAGAAAGACACCUGAGGCGUGGCCUCGGGCAGGUGAGAAGACACCUGAGGCGUGGCCUUGGGCAGGUGAGAAAGACAGGCAAGUUUCCAUAGUCCCAGAGGCUUCUUUCUCCUGGAUGGUGCGGCUCUGGGCUGUUUGGCUUCUCAGAGCUUCCUAAGAAGCUCCAUAAACGUGUGUGUGGACUGGCACAUUGUUUGUGUUCAUCGGCUUUUGGUUUUGAAACAUGUUGCAUUUUUUCAGAUUCAUGAUGGCUUGCAGAUGCUUGAUUUCCUGAAGGGGAGAACCUGAUGAGCUUGUCUUCUAGAUCAGUGGUCCCCAACCUUUUUGGCAUCAGGGACCAGCUUCCUGGAAGACCAGCUCCAUCUCUAGAGAAGCGGCCCAUGCUGUUGAUGACCUGAGUCUACAAGUUUCCUCACAAAUUGUAUUCAGAGAGCAGCUUCCUGCUUGGAAACAAUUCUGGUGAAAUGUGAUCGUCCUGGCCACCCUCUGAUUGAUAAGACAUAUCAUUUUGAAAGAUAUACUGGCCUUCCCAGCUGACAUGGACCUCAGGUCAGCUUCAGCGUGAGAAGCAGGCCAGGCCUGGGUCUGGAGCCGUCCUGGCCUUCCCAGAUGACAUGGACCUCAGGUCAGCUUCAGCGUGAGAAGCAGGCCAGGCCUGGGUCUGGAGCCGUCCUGGCCUUCCCAGAUGACAAGGACCUCAGGGUUUAUGGUCCAGCAGAGUCUCAGAGCGCGGUCUUUGGAGAUGUGUGCCCCCUACUCACUUCUCUCUUGGAUGGGUACAAUGUUUGUGUUAUGGCGUAUGGACAGACGGGCAGCGGAAAGAGCUAUACCAUGCUGGGACGCCAUUCGGACGACGGCCCUGUUCUGCCGCUUGACCCACAGAGUGACUUAGGAAUUAUCCCUAGAGUGGCUGAGGAGCUCUUCAGGCUCAUUUUGGAAAAUACCUCAAGAAGCCCAAAGGUUGAAGUCUCCAUAGUGGAAGUUUACAAUAAUGACAUUUUUGACCUUCUGGCCAAAGACAGCAUUGCAGCAGUGUCGGGGGUCAAGCGUGAGGUGGUGACAGCCAAGGAUGGACGGACAGAGGUUGCGCUGCUGGCCUCUGAGGCUGUCGGCAGCGCCUCGAAACUGAUGGAGCUCGUUCAUGGAGGUCUGCAGCUCAGGGCGAAGCACCCCACCCUGGUGCACGCGGAUUCCUCCAGGUCUCACCUGAUAAUUACGGUGACUCUAACCACAGCCUCCUGCUCUGACAGCACUGCAGACCAAGCCUGCAGUGCCACCCUCCCCAGGGAGCAAACAGAGGCAGGAAGGGCAGGAAGGAGCCGCAGAGCUUCUCAAGGGGCCUUGGCUCCACAGCUGGUUCCUGGGAACCCCGCAGGGCAUGCGGAGCAGGUGCAGGCUCGACUACAGCUCGUGGACUCGGCCGGCAGCGAGUGCGUUGGUGUGUCUGGAGUGACCGGGUUGGCCCUGAGGGAGAUGGCGUGCAUCAGCCGCAGCCUUGCGGCCCUGGCAGGCGUCCUGGGGGCUUUGUUGGAGCACCGUGGCCAUGCCCCGUACCGGAACAGCAGGCUCACCCACCUCCUUCAGGACUGCCUCGGAGGCGAUGCGAAGUUACUGGUGAUUCUCUGCAUUUCUCCCAGCCAGAGGCACCUGGCACAGACGUUGCAGGGCCUGGGUUUCGGGAUCCGAGCUCGGCAAGUCCAGCGAGGCCCUGCCCGAAAGAAGCCGCCCAGCUCCCAAACGGAGGGGAAGAGGAGGCCGGAUUGAAUGCAUUAACAAGUUUUUCUCCUAAAACUGUGUUUCUUGUCCUUGCUUUAUAAUGCAUAUGUGCUUAGAAAUAAACAGGUUUCACGUGGACUCAA